AGUUUGUUGCUCAAACCGAGUUCUGGAGAACGCCAUCAGCUCGCUGCUUAAAGGGAAAUGCUGUUGUGAGAGAGAAUGAGGAGAGAACUAGGUAAGGCUGUGAGAGCCAUCAGACCUCGAUGCAAGUCCACCCGCGAGGGAGGAAAAGAAGGAAACCAGGUUGAGUGGAAGCAUCCCAGACAGCUGUGCAGUCUAAGAGAACUUCAGCAAGCUGGAAACAAAAGUCUCAACUUCCAACCUCUUUGCAGCUAGGAGUGGCCAAGUAGCAUAGAUCUGGUGAAUGAACUGCAGGUGGGAAUUUCUGAGAAGGUUUCCUUCUUAAAUAGAAAGAUUAAACCACAGGUUCCAUUAUGGGUCGACUUGAUGGGAAAGUCAUCAUCCUGACGGCCGCUGCUCAGGGGAUUGGCCAAGCAGCUGCCUUAGCUUUUGCAAGAGAAGGUGCCAAAGUCAUAGCCACAGACAUUAAUGAGUCCAAACUUCAGGAACUGGAAAAGUACCCGGGUAUUCAAACUCGUGUCCUUGAUGUCACAAAGAAGAAACAAAUUGAUCAGUUUGCCAAUGAAGUUGAGAGACUUGAUGUUCUCUUUAAUGUUGCUGGUUUUGUCCAUCAUGGAACUGUCCUGGAUUGUGAGGAGAAAGACUGGGACUUCUCGAUGAAUCUCAAUGUGCGCAGCAUGUACCUGAUGAUCAAGGCAUUCCUUCCUAAAAUGCUUGCUCAGAAAUCUGGCAAUAUUAUCAACAUGUCUUCUGUGGCUUCCAGCGUCAAAGUUAUGGCAACUGAUGAUGAGAAACUAAGACUACCAAUGUUAAGAGUUGUGAACAGAUGUGUGUACAGCACAACCAAGGCAGCCGUGAUUGGCCUCACAAAAUCUGUGGCUGCAGAUUUCAUCCAGCAGGGCAUCAGGUGCAACUGUGUGUGCCCAGGAACAGUUGAUACGCCAUCUCUACAAGAAAGAAUACAAGCCAGAGGAAAUCCUGAAGAGGCACGGAAUGAUUUCCUGAAGAGACAAAAGACGGGAAGAUUCGCAACUGCAGAAGAAAUAGCCAUGCUCUGCGUGUAUUUGGCUUCUGAUGAAUCUGCUUAUGUAACUGGUAACCCUGUCAUCAUUGAUGGAGGCUGGAGCUUGUGAUUUUAGGAUCUCCAUGGUGGGAAGGAAGGCAGGCCCUUCCUAUCCACAGUGAACCUGGUUACGAAGAAAACUCACCAAUCAUCUCCUUCCUGUUAAUCACAUGUUAAUGAAAAUAAGCUCUUUUUAAUGAUGUCACUGUUUGCAAGAGUCUGAUUCUUUAAGUAUAUUAAUCUCUUUGUAAUCUCUUCUGAAAUCAUUGUAAAGAAAUAAAAAUAUUGAACUCAUAGCAGGAGAAUAGUUUUUAAAAUAAAUCUCGAUUUGUUAGCAUCUGUCUUAGUCACUUUGGGCUGCUAUAACAAAUUACCAUAGAUGGAGUGUCAUAGACAACAAACAUUUAUUUUUCAGUCUGGAGGCUAGGAAGUGCAAGAUAAAGGUGCCAGCAGAUAUAGUUUCUGGUUAGGGCCCACUUCCUGGUUUGCAGAUGGUCCUCUUCUUGCUGUAUCCUCACAUAGCAAGAGCAGAGAAAAAAAGCGAGCGCUCAUGUGUCUUUUUAUAAGGACACUAAUCCUGUUCAUGAGGGCACUACCCUUAUGACCUGAUUACCUCCCAAAGGCCCCACCUCCUAAUGUAUCAUAUUGCAGGUUAGGAUGUCAACACAUGACUCUGGGGUGAUACAAAUAGGCCAUUGCAGCAUAUACAAUUAAAAUGUAAAUAUGAAGAAAAAAGGAAGUUUUUGUUUUUUUGUGGGGGAGAUGGGGGUUAAGGAAGAAGAUAGUAAUUUCAGGACUAGGCAUGGUAGCUCAUGCCUAUAAUUCCUGCACUUUGGGAGGCCAAGGCAGGAGGAUCACUUGCGGCCAGGAGUUCAGGACCAGCAUGGUUAACAGAGGCUAAGGCAGGAGGAUUACUUGAGCCCAAGAGUUUGAGGCUGCAGUGAGCUGUAAUCAUGCCACUGCACUCCAGGGUGACAGAGCAAGACCCUGUACCUAAAUAAUAAUAAUAAUUUCCACUUCAUUUUUCAAUAUUCAAAUAUUUUUAUAUAAUUCUGCAUUGUUCUGUAUGUAGAUCCUAAUUUUAAAAUUUUACACCAUCAUAAAUGAACAAAGGUAGGAAGGAGUUUGGCUUCAAUAGCUUACAGUAAAAGGAGUAAAGGAGUUCAGCCUCAAAACGAUAUUGUUGACCUGUUAUGUUAUGAAAAAUAAUCCAGUGUUUAUACUUAACGGAUGCCAUCCCUUAUUAUUUACUAUUUUCUUAGUCUAACUAAACAAUCUUUAUUAAAAUAAGCAAUGAUAUUUGACAUGGGCCUAAGAAAUAUAUAGUUAGCUAACAAUAUUGUCAGUUAGAGGGAUUUCUUUUCUAAAUUAAGUACAGAUUUCUUCACCAAACUCCAGGAUAACAGAAAAGAGGACAUAAAAUUUGGACAUAGUUUCUGGAUAAAUAAAUGUAAAUUUAAAUAUAAAUUAUGUAACAGGAAACAAACGAAAUUAAAGAAAAUAAAUUUUUCAAGAAAAGUAAAUUUAUGGAUGUUAAUUCUGUAACAUUGUCAGGGCAAAGUUUUUUGUUUUUAUUUUAAUUUAAGGGUUUUAUGUUUGUUUUUUACUUGUUGCAACCUCAAAUGACCAAAUGGUAUGAUGCACACUGAGAUACUCAAUAAAUGUGCAGUGAUUCUUAGCCUUUUUUCCUAGAACUUUAAUAUUAACAUGGAAAAUUCUGAAAUGGACAACAAAAAGAUAACACUUUGUGUAUGGGGAAGAAUAUCAUGCAGUUGAUGACGGUACAUUAAAAUUCACACAAAAGGACAUUUUGACUAGCAUUCAGAAAGAGUCCAUUGAUUAUAAGAUUAUCUAUGAGGUUUUGGACCGGGCACUACACUACCGAAUUAUGGCUAACUUUGGUUUGUGAUCUAGACCAAGUCACCCAAUCUAUCUUGGAUUUUAGUUUUCUGGUUUAUGAAAUUAAGGAGUUAAGCUAAAUGACUUGGGUUUCUUUUCGUGUAUCAUAAUCAAAAUGCUGUAACUUCUCUAGUGAAUUCAUAGAACACUGACUCUUACAAGUAUGUCAUGAAAUACUUUAUGCUGUGAGCAGGUAUACAUGUAUAAUAUAUGUAUAGCUAUGAACAAAUAAAUUUUAAAUAAAUGCACAACGAAUUCUACAAAAUGGGCUCCAACAUUAA